AUUCACUCACUUCCUGAGGUGCCGAAGGACCCUGUGCUGCCUGUGACUUUGCUCCUAAGUACCUACUGCCGAGAUGUCCUGCCAGCAGAGCCAGCAGCAGUGCCAGCCCCCUCCCAAGUGCACUCCCAAGUGCCCUCCCAAGUGUCCCACCCCCAAAUGCCCUCCAAAGUGUCCCCCUAAGUGCCCUCCAGUCUCUUCCUGCUGCAGUGUCAGCUCCGGAGGCUGCUGUGGCUCCAGCUCUGGGGGCAGCUGUGGCUCCAGCUCUGGGGGCUGCUGCAGCUCUGGGGGAGGUGGCUGCUGCCUGAGCCACCACAGGCACCACAGGUCCCACCGUCACAGACCCCAGAGCUCUGACUGCUGCAGCCAGCCCUCAGGGGGCUCCAGCUGCUGUGGAGGGGGCAGCGGCCAGCACUCUGGAGGCUGCUGCUGAAGUGGACCUUGACUUCCUCUUCCUUCUGAUUCUGCCUGAAUAGCUGAGAGGUUCCAGCAAAAGCUUGAAGUCUUGCCUGGAGAAUCCCUCUGCUCUGGUGUCAGGAAACCCAAAAUCUUUCUCCUUAAUGGCAUUUAGAGACUUUCUUCUGCAGAUCCAUGGCUGCCCUGGGAACUCCAAAGCACACACCUACUUCCUCCCCAGCUCACGCUGCUGUAUUCUGUGCUGCCUGAACUGAAGAAAUAAAAUCCAGAAUCUGCCCCCCAACUUGCUACCAGCCUGCUUGAUUUUCCUGUUUGUGUCAUCCUUGUUCUGCUCCCCUGUGUCUGCUGGUGGCUGCUGAGGCCUUGGUGGACAGAGGAUGGGGAAAGGGGUCAGGAGGAAAAAGCUUGCAUUUCUGUGUGUUUUGUGUUUUUUCUUCUUUCGGUGUUUUCCUUUUAAACCAAGGGACUGAAAUAGCAUUGAGAAAUAUUUUUCUUUCAAAUUCUGGUUCCUUUCACCUAUGUAACCGCAUCCCUCAGGCAUGGCCAGGAGGCCGACUUCAUCCUCCUUCCCACUAUCACCUCUUCAUUCUUGUGUUCCUCGUUCCCCACUCCUUCCACUAACAAUCUCCCUGGACUCCUCCUCCAUACUGUAUGUGCAUGCAUUCACACACACAUAUGUACAUGCACAUAGAUGAGAUGAAUCUGCAUUGUAAAAAAAUUAAAUCACAUUUAGUGCUGUAUAAUUUGCAUGCAAUAAAAUUCAAUAAAAUUAAAUGUAAAAUUAAA